AUCUUCGUGCAGCCGCCGCGGGUCCGUGCGCCCAGCGUCCCAGGGCCCAGGCCGAGCAGACAAAGAUCAUUCCACUCAGCCUGGGACGAUGGGGAGGAAAAAAAUCCAGAUCUCCCGCAUCCUGGACCAAAGGAAUCGGCAGGUGACGUUCACCAAGCGGAAGUUCGGGCUGAUGAAGAAGGCCUAUGAGCUGAGCGUGCUCUGUGACUGUGAGAUAGCCCUCAUCAUCUUCAACAGCGCCAACCGCCUCUUCCAGUAUGCCAGCACGGACAUGGACCGUGUGCUGCUGAAGUACACAGAGUACAGCGAGCCCCACGAGAGCCGCACCAACACUGACAUCCUCGAGACGCUGAAGCGGAGGGGCAUUGGCCUCGAUGGGCCAGAGCUGGAGCCGGAUGAAGGGCCUGAGGAGCCAGGAGAGAAGUUUCGGAGGCUGGCAGGCGAAGGGGGUGAUCCGGCCUUGCCCCGACCCCGGCUGUAUCCUGCAGCUCCUGCUAUGCCCAGCCCAGAUGUGGUAUACGGGGCCUUACCGCCACCAGGCUGUGACCCCAGUGGGCUUGGGGAAGCACUGCCCGCCCAGAGCCGCCCAUCUCCCUUCCGACCAGCAGCCCCCAAAGCCGGGCCCCCAGGCCUGGUGCACCCUCUCUUCUCACCAAGCCACCUCACCAGCAAGACACCACCCCCACUGUACCUGCCGACGGAAGGGCGGAGGUCAGACCUGCCUGGUGGCCUGGCUGGGCCCCGAGGGGGACUAAACACCUCCAGAAGCCUCUACAGUGGCCUGCAGAACCCCUGCUCCACUGCAACUCCCGGACCCCCACUGGGGAGCUUCCCCUUCCUCCCCGGAGGCCCCCCAGAAUAUGGCCUGGGAGACCCUCCACCGCCCCCUGGCUUGUUGCAGCCCCCCACCCUGGCCCCCUGGCAGCCCUCGAGGGGUGAUGGGCCCCCCGCCGUGUCCUCCCAGCCCAGUGGGGGCCGAAGCCUGGGCGAGGAGGGUCCCCCAACCCGCGGCGCCUCCCCGCCGACCCCCCCAGUCAGCAUCAAGUCUGAGCGCCUCUCUCCGGCCCCCGGGGGCCCCGGCGACUUUCCUAAGACCUUCCCCUAUCCCUUGCUCCUCGCCCGGUCCCUGGCAGAGCCUCUGCGGCCUGGGCCCGCCCUGCGCCGGCUGCCCUUGGCCGACGGCUGGCCCCGGUAGGAGAUCACCCGGUGGCACCAGCCCAGAGCGCUCGCCAGGUACGGCGAGGGCACGUGGGGACCCCACCUCCCUCCAGGCCUCUUCAGAGAAGACCCAACAGUGACGCCCCCCUCCGCGGUGGGGGCUUGGAGGUGGGCGGCUGGACUCAAUCCACCCUGGGGGGCUCCUUUCCUUCUUCCUAUUUGUGUGUAUAUCCACAAAUAAAACGCGCGUGGCGUCCGUGGACCAGA